GAACCUUAACAGCCCUGCAGUGUAGUGGGCACUGGGCAGUGCUGCUCCUUCACUAAGCGGUCUGAGUUCUUUAGCUAUCUCGGAGAUUCAACUACGUUUACUCGUACUGAAUCUUUUUAAUGAAUUUCCUGAGAGCCAAGAAGGGCCAAUCUACAGGAAAAAGUGGGAGGUGGACAUUAAGCAUCUUCUAGAAACUCUUCUAGCUGAUAUCAUGAAACGACGACAAAAGAGGAAACAUUUGGAAAAUGAAGAGUCCCAGGAAACCGCUGAGAAGGGAGGAGGAAUGUCAAAGUCCCAAGAGGAUGCCCUGCAGCCUGGAUCCACUAGAGUGGCCAAAGGCUGGAGCCAAGGGGUGGGAGAAGUUACUUCUACCUCCGAAUACUGCUCCUGCGUUUCUUCUUCACGCAAGCUCAUCCACAGUGGAAUCCAGAGAAUACAUCGAGACAGCCCCCAGCCUCAAUCACCCCUGGCCCAGGUUCAGGAACGAGGAGAGACUCCUCCCCGCUCACAACAUGUCUCCUUGUCGUCCUAUUCAUCCUAUAAGACUUGUGUGUCCUCUCUGUGUGUAAACAAAGAGGAAAGGGGCAUGAAAAUAUACUACAUGCAGGUACAAAUGAACAAAGGUGUGGCUGUCUCCUGGGAGACAGAGGAAACUUUGGAGUCCUUAGAAAAGCAGCCAAGGAUGGAAGAAGUGACCCUUUCUGAGGUUGUGAGGGUAGGUACUCCCCCCUCUGAUGUGUCCACCAGAAACCUCCUGUCUGACAGUGAGCCCAGUGGGGAGGAGAAAGAGCAUGAGGAAAGGACAGAAUCAGACAGCCUGCCAGGCUCACCCACCGUUGAGGACACACCCAGAGCCAAGACUCCUGACUGGCUGGUGACCAUGGAGAACGGCUUCAGGUGCAUGGCCUGCUGCCGGGUGUUCACCACCAUGGAAGCCCUCCAGGAGCAUGUGCAGUUUGGGAUCAGAGAGGGCUUCAGCUGCCACGUCUUUCAUCUCACCAUGGCUCAGCUGACAGGCAACAUGGAAUCAGAGAGCACCCAAGAUGAGCAGGAGGAGGAAAAUGGAAAUGAGAAGGAGGAGGAAGAGAAACCAGAAGCAAAGGAGGAGGAGGGGCAGCCCACAGAAGAAGACCUUGGCCUGAGGAGAUCCUGGAGCCAAUGUCCAGGCUGUGUGUUUCAUUCUCCAAAGGACAGGAACAGCUGAGACUUAUGGGCCAGAAGAUACUGGAAGAUGGUGUGGCCUUCUCUUGCAAGAGGGAGAAGAAAGAGCCAUGGAGAUAGUAGCAGACAGGCUGCCCAAGGUAUGAAGCAGAUGAGGGACCAGCACUCAGUCUAACAUGUAAACAUCAUACGUAAUAAAGGUUGUGUUUCAAACCUUA